GUCUUCCUUCCCCUCCCUUGCAUGAUGGAAACACCAUGGCUGCGGCGGCCCAGCUCUCUCUGACACAGUUAUCAAGUGGGAAUCCUGUAUAUGAAAAAUACUAUAGACAGGUUGAUACAGGCAAUACUGGAAGGGUGUUGGCUUCUGAUGCUGCUGCUUUCCUGAAAAAAUCAGGGCUUCCAGACUUGAUACUUGGAAAGAUUUGGGAUUUAGCCGACACAGAUGGCAAAGGUAUCCUGAACAAACAAGAAUUCUUUGUUGCUUUGCGUCUUGUGGCAUGUGCCCAGAAUGGAUUGGAAGUUUCACUAAGUAGUUUGAACCUGGCUGUUCCUCCACCAAGAUUUCAUGAUACCAGUAGUCCUUUGCUAAUCAGUGGAACCUCUGCAGCUGAGCUCCCAUGGGCUGUAAAACCUGAAGAUAAGGCCAAAUAUGAUGCAAUAUUUGAUAGUUUAAGCCCAGUGAAUGGAUUUCUGUCUGGUGAUAAAGUGAAACCAGUGUUGCUCAACUCUAAGUUACCUGUGGAUAUCCUUGGAAGAGUUUGGGAGUUGAGUGAUAUUGACCAUGAUGGAAUGCUUGACAGAGAUGAGUUUGCAGUUGCCAUGUUUUUGGUAUACUGUGCACUGGAGAAAGAACCUGUGCCAAUGUCCUUGCCUCCAGCCUUGGUGCCACCAUCUAAGAGAAAAACGGUCAGUAUAUCAGGCUCUGUGCGGUUGAUCCCCUCUUCAGCAUCAGCCAAGGAAUCUUACCACUCCUUACCAUCUGUAGGCAUUUUACCUACCAAAGCACCAUUAAGACAGUGGGUUGUAUCCCCUGCAGAAAAAGCUAAAUAUGAUGAAAUCUUCCUGAAAACUGAUAAAGAUAUGGACGGAUUUGUGUCUGGAUUGGAGGUCCGUGAAAUAUUCUUGAAAACAGGUUUACCUUCUACCUUACUAGCCCAUAUAUGGUCAUUAUGCGACACAAAGGACUGUGGGAAGCUUUCAAAGGAUCAGUUUGCCUUGGCUUUUCACUUAAUCAGUCAGAAGUUAAUCAAGGGCAUUGAUCCUCCUCACGUUCUUACUCCUGAAAUGAUUCCACCAUCAGACAGGGCCAGUUUACAAAAGAACAUCAUAGGAUCAAGUCCUGUUGCAGAUUUCUCUGCUAUUAAGGAACUAGAUACUCUUAACAAUGAAAUAGUUGACCUACAGAGGGAAAAGAAUAAUGUGGAACAGGACCUUAAGGAGAAGGAAGAUACUAUUAAACAGAGGACAAGUGAGGUUCAGGAUCUUCAAGAUGAAGUUCAAAGGGAGAAUACUAAUCUGCAAAAACUACAGGCCCAGAAACAGCAGGUACAGGAACUCCUUGAUGAACUGGAUGAGCAGAAAGCCCAGCUGGAGGAGCAACUCAAGGAAGUCAGAAAGAAAUGUGCUGAGGAGGCCCAACUGAUCUCUUCUCUGAAAGCUGAAUUAACUAGUCAGGAAUCGCAGAUCUCCACUUACGAAGAAGAAUUGGCAAAAGCUAGAGAAGAGCUGAGCCGUCUACAGCAAGAAACAGCAGAAUUGGAGGAGAGUGUAGAGUCAGGGAAGGCUCAGUUGGAACCUCUUCAGCAGCACCUACAAGAUUCACAACAGGAAAUUAGUUCAAUGCAAAUGAAACUGAUGGAAAUGAAAGAUUUGGAAAAUCAUAAUAGUCAGUUAAAUUGGUGCAGUAGCCCACACAGCAUUCUUGUAAACGGAGCUACAGAUUAUUGCAGCCUCAGCACCAGCAGCAGUGAAACAGCCAACCUUAAUGAACAUGUUGAAGGCCAGAGCAACCUAGAGUCUGAGCCCAUACACCAGGAAUCUCCAGCAAGAAGUAGUCCUGAACUACUGCCUUCUGGUGUGACUGAUGAAAAUGAGGUGACUACAGCUGUUACUGAAAAAGUUUGUUCUGAACUCGACAAUAAUAGACAUUCAAAAGAGGAAGAUCCAUUUAAUGUAGACUCAAGUUCGCUGACAGGUCCAGUUGCAGAUACAAACUUGGAUUUUUUCCAGUCUGAUCCUUUUGUUGGCAGUGAUCCUUUCAAGGAUGAUCCUUUUGGAAAAAUCGAUCCAUUUGGUGGUGAUCCUUUCAAAGGUUCAGAUCCAUUUGCAUCAGACUGUUUCUUCAGGCAAUCUACUGAUCCUUUUGCCACUUCAAGCACUGACCCUUUCAGUGCAGCCAACAAUAGCAGUAUUACAUCGGUAGAAACGUUGAAGCACAAUGAUCCUUUUGCUCCUGGUGGAACAGUUGUUGCAGCAAGCGAUUCAGCCACAGACCCCUUUGCUUCUGUUUUUGGGAAUGAAUCAUUUGGAGGUGGAUUUGCUGACUUCAGCACAUUGUCAAAGGUCAACAAUGAAGAUCCUUUUCGUUCAGCCACAUCGAGCUCUGUCAGCAACGUAGUGAUUACAAAAAAUGUAUUUGAGGAAACAUCGGUCAAAAGUGAAGAUGAACCCCCAGCACUGCCACCAAAGAUCGGAACUCCAACAAGACCCUGCCCUCUACCACCUGGGAAAAGAUCCAUCAACAAAUUGGAUUCUCCUGAUCCCUUUAAACUGAAUGAUCCAUUUCAGCCUUUCCCAGGCAACGAUAGCCCCAAAGAAAAAGAUCCUGAAAUAUUUUGUGAUCCAUUCACUUCUGCUACUACCACUACCAAUAAAGAGGCUGAUCCAAGCAAUUUUGCCAACUUCAGUGCUUAUCCCUCUGAAGAAGAUAUGAUCGAAUGGGCCAAGAGGGAAAGUGAGAGAGAGGAAGAGCAGAGGCUUGCCCGACUAAAUCAGCAGGAACAAGAAGACUUAGAACUGGCUAUUGCACUCAGCAAAUCUGAGAUAUCAGAAGCAUGAAGAAUUCUCUUGUUCUUUGGCAACAAUAUAGUAUUCUUCUUCCUGAAUACUGAAACUAUUUACAAUGUGUAUCAAAACUACCUGUGAGCAUGGGAAUACAAAAGGUUUGAGAUUCCUGUAAAUGUGACAAAAUUUUAGGAUUUUUUUUUUUUCUUCAUUACAGAUUCGUCUUUUUUUUUUUUUCUUAUAAAAGCCGUAACCCAGUCAGACAAAUUCACCUUCACUUAGGCCCCUGUUCUGGUAUACAUUUACUGUGAGCUUUUGCCUGCCUGUGCUAUUUUACUUGUAAAGCUAGAGCACCCAAGCUUCUGCCUUCUGGAAUAUAGAGAAAUAGUUUCACCCUGCACUACCCUGUUCUGUAGUUAUUCUGAUGAUAGCCAGUGAGGUUCUUAAAGUUUGCAGUAUUCUCCCCUGAUUGGAAUGGUUGAGUGAGGGUAAGGGAAAGAAUAUCUUAUUUCUUUUAUGAUUGGUGCAAAUUGGCUAAAGUGCAUUUUUAAAUUUCCUCUACUUAAUUUGUUUUUCAGAGAUAAGGAAAAAUAUUUUGCACAGAUUUACUCCACUAUGGAAAAGGGAUGCUGUAGGUUGAACCAUUAUAGCCUCAGAUUCGAUCUUUUCCUAACUAAAAAUAUUAAAGCCUCAUGUGUGAAAUAAAUUUUUAAAAAGAUUUAUCUGGAUUUAGAGAAUUUUAGAUCAACAGAUACCUCUCAGUGUGUUUGCUAAUUAAUAAAAAUCAGUUUCUUACAAAUAAAGUUUGUAAGAAAAUGUUCAUUUUAAGUGAUAGAUAGUGGAGAAAAUUUAUCACCUAAAAUAUACCCAUCAGUAUAAGGCAAGCAAAAGUCUUAACAUGGCAGCCAUUCUGCCUUUGCCGUGGCCCUGUCCUGUUUAGUUCUUAGUGGGUUAAUUUUUGUACUUUUGCAGAAGAAACUUCAGCAAGCUAGAACUGGAAGGUACUUUAAUUUUUCAUAUAUAUUUGUUUUUUUUUUUUUAAUGAAGGCUCAUUUACUUGAAAUGUAAAAACUUUCACUGAAUACAAAUAGAAAAAGUGAUGUGUUUUAUAUCAUAUUGCUUUUUGUCCAUCUUUGUGGUUUAGUUUAUUUACUCACUUCAUGUUUUUCACCUAUAAAAUUGUCAAGCUAGCAAAAAAACUCUUGUUUUUUUAAUUGGGAGAGAAGAGACCUGCCAGAUUAUCAGACCUCUUCAUGUUAAAAGACCAUCUCCUGUAAAACUGACCUAGUGGACAAGCUGAAUUUGAAAUAGACUGUGAAGUAAGCUGUAACUUGUCAUUUUAAUUUUGUUUAACACGGUUACUGACUUAGAUGAUGUAUUAAAUACCAAGAUAAAGAAAAAUGCACCUAAAAUCUAAUUAGAAUUCUCUGGGUCAACAAGUCAAGGUGGUAUUGAUCUGUGUUAAUCUGAGUAACUUAUUGCCUAGCCUAUAAAUAAAUUCCAAAAUAUCCAAUUCAUUUCUUCUUGAAAUGGUGCUUGUUUUGUUUUCUUUCCAUUACACAAUUAGACUCCUACAGUUUAAAACAAACUUUAAACCACUAUCUUGCACUGCUAACUUUUUUCUACCUUUGUAAAUAGAAACAUUUCUGCAUAAAAGUCAUACAUAUGAAGCAAGGGCUGAAUCAUAAUCACAAGGCUUAAUUUUGAUAAACGAAUCCAGUGACCUAAGGAUUUUCUGCAAAAUUUGACUGGGAGUUGUGAUAGGUGGUAUUUUUGUUUAUUUUCUUCCUCUUACUCCUUAGGAUAAAGGUAAGUUGACUUGAACAACUUUCUUUUGCACUGGGAAAAUAAGCAAAUGUUUAAAUGCUUCAAAAAAAUUUUCAAUUAAACUCAAAUAUUAAAUAUCUAUAACUUAUAAACACCAACUUUCAAUGUAAUAAAUGUAUCCUAAUCUUAUGUAUGUUUAACUGGAUUACAUAGAUUUUUAUCUUUUGUUAAAAUGUGUAUACCCCGUGGACCAACAUAAUAUUAAAGUAUGUAUAUAUUAUAUAAAUAUAUAUGUAUAUGUGCUCGCUUGUGUAGGAUGAAUGUCUUAGAGUCGUUUGUGGUAUUUUAUGUUGUUGACUCUGGCUCCAGGGCCUGUGCUUGAAAAGGACAGAUAAGUAUUGCCCAGAGCUAAGUGGCACUACUUACAAAGUUUUAAAUGUCUUCUACAUACUGAUUCAUGUUUAUUUGAGCUCUCUUUAUAGAAUUUUCUCUUAAAGUUUCAAACCUCUAAGUUGUAGCCUGUAAUUAUGAGAACAGUAAACUUUAAGUAAUAAUAAAGAAUCCCAUCCAUAUAUCCAAUUUGCAAUUGAGUUUUGCAUGGUUCUCUGAUUAUGUCCAUGCUGUGUCCAAGGAGGAGUAGGUACAUACAAUCAGCACAGAUUAAUAUAUGUAAAGGGUUUGGGACAGCACCUGGUAUAGAAUAAAUAAUAAAUGUAAACUAUUA